AGGGAAGGGGAGCGCCCGCCCCUUCCCUGCCGCCGCGAGCGCCCCGGGAGGGGACCGGGGCUGCCGUCCCUCCGCCUCUUCCCCCGCGGGGCGUAGCGAUGGCCCGGGCCAGGGCCGGGGCGCUGCUGGCGCUUUGGGUGCUCGGGGCCGCCGCGCAUCCGCAGUGCCUGGACUUCAGGCCGCCCUUCCGGCCGACGCAGCCGCUGCGCCUCUGCGCGCAGUACUCGGACUUCGGCUGCUGCGAUGAGGGGCGCGACGCCGAGCUGACCCGCCGCUUCUGGGCCCUGGCGAGCCGCGUGGACGCCGCCGAGUGGGCCGCGUGCGCCGGCUACGCGAGGGACCUGCUGUGCCAGUUUCCCCUCCUGAAGCAGGAAGGACGGACGGACGGACAGAUGAUGUCAUCAUUUCCUCAGAGGUUGGGGGCUCUUCUGCCCCAGUCCCCUGGAGUCGACCCCUCAGCGUCCCACCCCGAGCAGCUGCACCCUUGUCGGGGUACCAAGGUGGAGAGGCAUCUGUCCCGGAAUGCUCGCCGUAUGCAGCCCACCUCUAUGACGCCGAGGACCCAUUCACGCCCCUGCGCACGGUGCCCGGGCUCUGCCAGGAUUACUGCCUGGACAUGUGGCAUAAGUGCCGGGGGCUGUUCCGUCACCUGUCAACUGACCAGGAGCUCUGGGCGCUGGAGGGCAACCUUGCCAGGUUCUGCCGCUACCUGUCCCUGGAUGACACGGACUACUGCUUCCCUUACCUGCUGGUCAACAAGAACCUCAACUCAAACCUGGGCCACGUGGUAGCCGAUGCCAAGGGCUGCCUGCAGCUGUGCCUGGAGGAGGUGGCCAACGGGCUGCGCAACCCCGUGGCCAUGGUCCAUGCCAGGGAUGGCACCCACCGCUUCUUCGUGGCCGAGCAGGUGGGGCUGGUGUGGGCCUACCUGCCCGACCGCUCGAGGCUGGGGAAGCCUUUCCUGAACAUCAGCCGGGUGGUGCUCACCUCGCCCUGGGAGGGUGACGAGCGUGGCUUCCUGGGCAUUGCCUUCCACCCCAGCUUCCAGCACAACCGCAGGCUCUACGUCUACUACUCAGUGGGUAUCCGCAGCAGUGAGUGGAUCCGCAUCAGCGAGUUCAGAGUCUCCGAGGAUGACGAGAACGCCGUGGACCACAGCUCUGAGAGGAUAAUCCUGGAGGUCAAAGAACCAGCCUCAAACCACAACGGGGGCCAGCUGCUUUUCGGGGAUGACGGGUACCUCUACAUCUUCACUGGAGAUGGCGGGAUGGCCGGAGACCCCUUUGGGACAUUUGGAAAUGCCCAAAACAAGUCGGCGCUGCUGGGCAAGGUGCUGCGCAUCGACGUGGACCGUAAGGAGCGCGGCCUGCCCUACGGCAUCCCGCCCGACAACCCGUUCGUGGGCGACCCCGCGGCGCAGCCCGAGGUCUACGCCCUGGGCGUGCGCAACAUGUGGCGCUGCUCCUUCGACCGUGGCGACCCCUCCUCGGGCACUGGCCGCGGGCGCCUCUUCUGCGGCGACGUGGGCCAGAACAAGUUCGAGGAGGUGGACGUGGUGGAGCGCGGCGGCAACUAUGGCUGGCGCGCGCGCGAAGGGUUCGAGUGCUACGACCGCAGCCUGUGCGCCAACACCUCUCUCAAUGACUUGCUGCCGAUUUUCGCCUACCCGCACACGGUUGGCAAGUCGGUCACAGGGGGCUACGUGUACCGGGGCUGCGAGUACCCCAACCUGAACGGCCUCUACAUUUUUGGGGAUUUCAUGAGCGGGCGUCUGAUGUCCCUCCAAGAGAACCCAGGGACAGGCCAGUGGCAGUACAGUGAGAUCUGCAUGGGCCACGGCCAGACCUGUGAGUUCCCAGGCCUCAUCAACAACUACUACCCGUACAUCAUCUCCUUCGGGGAGGACGAGGCCGGGGAGCUGUACUUCAUGUCGACAGGGGAGCCGAGUGCCACAGCUCCACGCGGAGUUGUCUACAAAAUAAUUGACGCAUCCAGGCGGGCACCACCUGGCAAAUGUCAGAUCCAGCCUGCUCAGGUGAAGAUCAGAAGCCGUCUCAUCCCCUUUGUGCCCAAAGAAAAGUUCAUCCCGAAGACACGGAGCACCCCGCGGCCUACAGCGCGGGCGCCCACGCGGGCGCCCCGCCGAGGGCGCCCCACGGCCGCUCCCCCCGCGCCAACCCCGCGGCCAGCGCGGCCCACCCAGCAGCCAGGGAGCCGGAGGGGCGGCGGGCGGCGGCGGGGGCGGCUGAACUCGGCGAGCCGGGCGUUCCGGGAUGGCGAGGUGCGCCUGGUGCGGCCCGCGGGCCUGAGCUCUGGCAGCGGGCGCGUGGAGGUGUUCGUGGGCGGACGCUGGGGCACCGUGUGCGACGACUCCUGGAACAUCAGCGGCGCCGCCGUCGUGUGUCGCCAGCUGGGGUUUGCCUACGCCGUGCGCGCCGUCAAGAGAGCCGAGUUCGGCCAGGGCGGCUCGCUGCCCAUUCUGCUGGACGAUGUGCGCUGCGCGGGCUGGGAGCGGAACCUGCUGGAGUGCCAGCACAACGGCGUGGGCACCCACAACUGCGAGCACGACGAGGAUGCGGGCGUCGUGUGCAGCCACCAGAACCCCGACCUGUAGGCAACACGCCGCUGCCCCAGGCCAUCCCGCCGGCGGGGGAGCCUGGCAGGGGCCGCUCCGCCCUGUGUGCGCCCAGCGGGUGCACACGUGUUCUAGAGUGAAGGGGGUGCGGGUGUGUGCUGUCCUGGGGACAUGUGUGAGGCGCUGCAGUGCAUGUGUGUCCUCUGCAGACCCAAGGCAGGAGUGUGUGUUGGGGGCGGUGUGGGCUCUGGAAGUGCAUGGUCCAUCAUGGGCGGGAGGAGUUCCUUUCUUACCUCCAAGCGUUUCAGACACCAGCAGGAACAGCAGCCGGGCUGUGGGACCCUGAGGAGGGAGGGCAGCCAGGCUUCGAGGACGGACAUGGCCCCUGGCUGUGCUAACAGAGGCACAGCUUGCAGACUGAGGGCGGUGGGGAGAACCAGGCUUGUCCUGCCCACAGCUGGAAUGGAAGGUGCAAGAACAGCCGGAGGGUGGCCUGAGGAAUGUGGCCCGGACAGCAUGGCCUGGUGCCCGCAUCCCCCCCACCCCCUGGCAGUCAGAGGCGCUGGAGAGAACCGGAAGGCAUCCAGUGGGGAAGGGAAAGCCUUCUGGAAGGUGGGAGCAGGGUGAGCUGCAGGCCUGGGGCCCCACUGGAGGGGCAGGCUGCGUGGAGGAGCCAGCACCUGCUCAGGGAGGAUGGCUGUGAGGACUGGAUGACCUCCAAGGCCGUAUGCUGGAGAAGCCACUCAGCAGCAUACUCAGUCCUUGUGGGUGCUCCUGGGAUGGGACCAGCCUCCUCCAACCCUGAGGCCUGAUUCUCUCUUGCUCUUGGGGCAGAAGCCACCCACACUAGCUGGGCAGAGCUUUCACCCUGGCCCUCCAGUGAGUCGGUGGGCCUCCACUACUUUCAAAGCUGUGUUUGGGCCCUGGGGCCACCUCUGUCCUUUCCAUCCCCAUCCCUGCUCAGUGUAAACCCAGGAGACCUGAUUCCUCCAGCCCUACCUCGGGGCUGACCAGGCUGGGGGUCCAGUGAAACUACUGACACUUUUUCACCCAGGGCUAUGCCAAUAAUGUGGCUGUUUACACACCACUUUCCUGCCUCCUCUCUGACCUGCACCUGUGUGGGAGCCGGGGUGGGAACCAGGAGAAAGGGGUGAGGCCUCCCGCUUCCCACCUGCAUCACAGGUGGAAGCUCCUUCACUCCAGGGAUGCUCGGCCCUGGCUCUGUGCCAGGCCGCAGAGGGGCACUUAGUAUGACUGCGCUCAGCCUCGGAUGGGAGCACGGGUGGGGGGUGGGUAAGCAGAUGAGUCACCAGGCAGUGAAGACAGGAUGUGGCCCAUGUCGGGGGUUGGAAGAGGUCUGGGUGGGGCACCCAAACCCAACCUAUGGGGGGGCUUUGGGAGGGGGUGAUGCUGUGCCAAGUUCUGGGAGCUGGCACCAGGGGUGGCUGGGCAGGCCUUGGGGCAGGCAUGAGUCUGGCAGGGUCUCCUAGCUGCUAGUAUAGGGUCUCCUAGCCACUAGUAUAGGAUCCUGGGCUGCAGCAGAAAGCUUUAGGUCACUGUCUUGGACUCCUCAUACUCUGUGCUUUACAGAAUGGGAAACUGAGGCACACAGAGGUUAGAUAUCUUAGGGCACCAAGCCAGGGAAGGGAGAAGUCAAGUUUGAAUACAGCAGCUUAGUUUAGAGUCCCCGCACCCUAACCACUGCCCUCCCCAGCUACACUAUGCCUGCAGAGAGCGGUGUGCUGGGGCUCCUGCCUGGUGUGGGAGUGCCAGCCUGGCUGGGAAGCAGCUGAUGGAGAUCCCUGGGGGCUCCUCUUGCCUGGCAGGUGCCCCCGCUGCUGGCCUCAUGCUCCUCUCGGGCCUCCAGUGGCCCAGGGGAGGUUGAGUGGGCAUCUUCCUGGGAUGCAGGGGAGUUCUGAGCUCUGACGCCGGGCGUGUUAGGAGAUAGCAGGCCGUUAAUGACCAUCCCAGCCGAAUUCCUCACUGUGCAGAUGAGGAAGUGAGCUCAGGGAGGCUGAGUGUCCCAGGCCUGUUGCCAGAUGAGGCCACGCUGAGACUGGAGCCAGGGAAGGUGCAGCAAGCCUUGAGGCCCUCAAGAAUGCAGCCGAGCCAGGGCCCUGCUUGCCUGGCCCCAGAAGCUGUUUUGCUCAGAGCUGGAUUAGGAGGGUUGGCAAAGGGAGCUCUGGGUGCGGCCUCAGGCCCUCCAGUACUUCUCUGGGCAGUUCGGGCUUUGGCCUUCAGUCUUCCAGGCCAGGCGCUCUUCCUCCCCAGCCUCCAACUCAUCACCUCUCAGGCCCCAAACCAGGCCUGGGCUAGGCUGCAGCCUGCCUCCUGGGGACUCACUCCACAGUCCCCAGGUCAGUGGUCCCCAACCUUUUUGGCAUCAUGGACUGGUUUCAUGUAAGACAAUUUUUCCAUGGAUGGGGGUUGGGGGGAUGGUUUUGGGAUGAAAUGUCCCACCUCAGAUCAUCAGGCAUUAGAUUCUCAUAAGGAGUUCACAGCCUAGAUCCCUCGCAUGCACAGUUCAUAGUAGGUUUCAUGUUCCUAUGCGGAUCUAAUGCCACUGCUGAUCUGGCAGGAGGCAGAGCUCAGGUGGGAAUGCUUGCUCCCCACACUACCCUGCCCCACUGCCACUCACCUCCUGCUGUGUGGCCCGGUUCCUAACAGGCCACCCAUCAGUACUGGUCCGUGGCCCAGGGUUUGGAGACCUCUGCCCUAGGUAGUAAUAAGAGUGGACAGCUGUUAUAUGUAAAUACUUGUUCCCCGAUGCUGGAAAGAAAUAGCACUAAAACAUAAAUUUAAUUCUUUCAGCAAGGCAAUUUUACUUUCUGCAGAAAGGGUGCUCAUCGCAGAUGGAACAAUAGUGAGAGGACACCUGAACAAAGGAGGGAAGCAAUUGUUAGCCCUUAUGCAGUUUGUCCCUGCUACUGUGUCCUAUGUCCAUUGGCAGAAGCCAGACCGCACAAUCUAAACUAAAACCCGAUUGGCUGUUUAAAAUUUUUCUAAAUAGGUAAAAGUAAUGGAAGGAUAAAGGAAAAGAGGAAGUUGCUUACGAAAGGACUUAGAAAAGUAAUAAUAUUCCCAAAUAAGGAAGGGGUAUAGGCUGUGAGCUGGGACAUGCCUGUGAGCACGUCCAGCACAGAUAUCUUGGUUAAAGUAUAAGGACAUAGAACGUACUAUGUGCCUGUGAGCACGUCUAACAGUUACAUAGAAUAGGGCUUGACAAAGAGUUAUUAGCAUAAAGCAAGGAGGUUUGAAGGAAGUUCGUCUUUAAAAGAAACCAUUAUUUCUAACACUUACGAUUUAUUCUUUAACAAGAAGGGAAACUUUCAAGAGGAACUUUUACUUUCUACAACAGCUGACCUCUGCUGAGCGCUUACUACAUGCCAAGCACUGCUCUGAAAGUUUAACAUACCAUUCACUCAUGUAAUCCUCAUAUUAAUGCACAUUUACUCACGUGGAAGCCGAGUUCCAGGGCAUUUGUCACUUACCAAAUGUCACAUAGCCAAAAUUUGAAUUUGAGCCCAGGUAGUCCAGCUCUGGGACCCUGCUGUGGGCCUUCCUGCUGGGCCACCUCAAGGGCAUUGAAAGCCAGCCCCACCCCACUGGGACACAAGUUCAGAGAAGGGCAGAGCUGGCUGCCUGUCCAGUGCUUCUUUCACUCCACCACCUACAGCUGGCCGCUGAGGGAGCAUUCACAUGUGACUCUGUCCCCAGGGACUCCGAUCUUGCCUUAAAGUCCUCCAGGGCCUCUGAGGAUGGGGGCACAGCCUUCACCCUCACCCCCUCUAAUCCAACCUCUAGUCAAUAGCCAGGAUCAGAUUCUCAGAGAGGGGCUGCCCUGCCCAGUGCCACACAGCUUAGUGCUGGAGCCUCAGGGUCAAUGCUGCAGGGGUGGCCCAGUGUCCAGGACUGUGUUCAAGACAUCAGUCAGAGGUCACAACAUCCCAGGCCCUAGACUGAGCCUAGGGGUCACCAUGUUGAUACCUUAGAAAUGUUUGGGAGGUUCAAGGAAGCUGGAAACUGGGUUCCAGUCCUGGCUCUGUGCCUCUCUGAGUCUCAUUGCAAAAUAGAGGUCACCAGAAGGAUUACUGGAUGAAAAAUGAGGUAGCAUUGCAGACGUGCAUGGCACGUACACUCUAGGUUGCUUCCUAGACAGAAAGCUCAGUUCGAGGCUGGUGGCAUCCAUGCUGGCAGCAGCCAACUGUCUGCGACAGAGUGAGGAGGGGCAUGCCACGUGAAGGACCAGCAUCAGAAUGACAUGGGAAGAAACUCUCACAAUAGCAGAAGAAAGAGCUCCUUCAGCCUAACAUGUAGAACUCAAGUCUUCUUGUCGCGCUUCUGUCCCCUCGCCCCUCCUCCCCCACUGAGAACUAGCUUUUACUGAGCAGUUAUUACAUGCCAGCUACCUCGGGUGUGUCAGCUCAUUUAAUCUUGACAACAGCUCCACGAGACACCCUCAAUAUCACUGUCCCUGUUUUCCAGAUGAGGGGACAGAUUCCUAGGGUGUUAUGUAAGUGGUCCCCGGGGCUUUAGAGGCAGGUUUGCACCAAGGCCCAUUCUCCCAGAGCCGGAUCCUUCUCCUUCCCUGGGAUACAGCACCUCCACCCUGCCAGGCCACCCAUGUAAAGGCAGCCAAUUCAGAGCCACCUCUUAUGCCUGCAUCUCCCCAACAAUUCCUGCUGGGAAACCACUCCUCGUAUGGUGUCAUCUACACCAGUGGGUUUCAAGCUUGAGAAGAAUCAAGUUCUACAGGGCUGCUUAAAACACAGGUUGCUGGGUCCUGUCUCUCAGAGUUUUUGACUCAGUCUUGGUUGAGAAUUUUCAGUUCUAGAAGCUCCUGGGUAAUGCUAAUCCUCCUGUUCUAGGGGCCAUAGUCAUUGUCCAUACUGGUGCUAUCCAAUAGAAACAUAAUGUGAGCCAAAUAGGUAAUUUAAAAUCUGCUUGUAGCCAUGUUAAAAAAGUAAAACAGGUAAAAUUAA